GGGCCGCGAGAGGCGCCGGGAUCGCGGGCGCCGGCUGAGCCAGCGGCUCUUGGGAGGCUGCGUCCGCGCGCCGGCGAGGCGAGGCGGCCGGGCCCUGCGCGUCAGGCCUGAGACCUGGGAGGAAGCUGGAGAAAAGAUGCCCUCUGAAUCUUUCUGUUUGGCUGCCCAGGCUCGCCUCGACUCCAAAUGGUUGAAAACAGAUAUACAGCUUGCAUUCACAAGAGAUGGGCUCUGUGGUCUGUGGAAUGAAAUGGUUAAAGAUGGAGAAAUUGUAUACACUGGAACAGAAUCAACCCAGAACGGAGAGCUCCCUCCUAGAAAAGAUGAUAGUGUCGAACCAAGUGGAACAAAGAAAGAAGAUCUGAAUGACAAAGAGAAAAAAGAUGAAGAAGAAACUCCUGCACCUAUAUAUAGGGCCAAGUCAAUUCUGGACAGCUGGGUAUGGGGCAAGCAACCAGAUGUGAAUGAACUGAAGGAGUGUCUUUCUGUGCUGGUUAAAGAGCAGCAGGCCCUGGCCGUCCAGUCAGCCACCACCACCCUCUCAGCCCUGCGACUCAAGCAGAGGCUGGUGAUCUUGGAGCGCUAUUUCAUUGCCUUGAAUAGAACCGUUUUUCAGGAGAAUGUCAAAGUUAAGUGGAAAAGCAGCGGUAUUUCUCUGCCUCCUGUGGACAAAAAAAGUUCCCGGCCUGCGGGCAAAGGUGUGGAGGGGCUCGCCAGAGUGGGAUCCCGAGCGGCGCUGUCUUUUGCCUUUGCCUUCCUGCGCAGGGCCUGGCGAUCAGGCGAGGAUGCGGACCUCUGCAGUGAGCUGUUGCAGGAGUCCCUGGACGCCCUGCGAGCACUUCCCGAGGCCUCGCUCUUUGACGAGAGCACCGUGUCCUCUGUGUGGCUGGAGGUGGUGGAGAGAGCGACCAGGUUCCUCAGGUCCGUCGUGACGGGGGAUGUUCACGGAACGCCAGCCACCAAAGGGCCAGGAAGCAUCCCCCUGCAGGACCAGCACUUGGCCCUGGCCAUCCUGCUGGAGCUGGCUGUGCAGAGAGGCACGCUGAGCCAAAUGUUGUCUGCCAUCCUGUUGUUGCUUCAGCUGUGGGACAGCGGGGCACAGGAGACUGACAAUGAGCGUUCCGCCCAGGGCACCAGCGCCCCACUUUUGCCCUUGCUGCAAAGGUUCCAGAGCAUCAUUUGCAGGAAGGAUGCACCCCACUCCGAGGGCGACAUGCACCUUUUGUCUGGCCCUCUGAGCCCCAAUGAGAGUUUCCUGAGGUACCUCACCCUUCCACAAGACAACGAGCUUGCCAUUGAUCUGCGACAAACGGCGGUUGUUGUCAUGGCCCAUUUAGACCGUCUGGCUACGCCCUGUAUGCCUCCGCUGUGUAGCUCUCCGACAUCUCAUAAGGGAUCAUUGCAAGAGGUCAUAGGUUGGGGGUUAAUAGGAUGGAAAUACUAUGCCAAUGUGAUUGGUCCAAUCCAGUGCGAAGGCCUGGCCAACCUGGGAGUCACACAGAUUGCCUGUGCAGAGAAGCGUUUCCUGAUUCUGUCACGCAAUGGCCGCGUGUACACACAGGCCUAUAAUAGUGACACGCUGGCCCCACAGCUGGUCCAAGGCCUUGCCUCCAGAAACAUUGUAAAAAUUGCUGCCCAUUCUGAUGGUCACCACUACCUAGCCUUGGCUGCUACUGGAGAGGUGUACUCCUGGGGCUGUGGGGACGGCGGACGGCUGGGCCAUGGGGACACUGUGCCUUUGGAGGAGCCUAAGGUGAUCUCCGCCUUCUCUGGAAAGCAGGCCGGGAAGCACGUGGUGCACAUCGCUUGCGGGAGCACUUACAGUGCGGCCAUCACUGCCGAGGGGGAGCUGUACACCUGGGGCCGCGGGAACUACGGCCGGCUGGGCCAUGGCUCCAGUGAGGACGAGGCCAUUCCGAUGCUGGUAGCCGGGCUUAAAGGACUGAAGGUCAUCGAUGUGGCGUGUGGGAGUGGGGAUGCUCAAACCCUGGCUGUCACUGAGAACGGGCAAGUGUGGUCUUGGGGAGAUGGUGACUAUGGGAAAUUGGGCAGAGGUGGUAGUGAUGGCUGCAAAACCCCAAAGCUGAUUGAAAAGCUUCAAGACUUGGAUGUGGUCAAAGUCCGCUGUGGAAGUCAGUUUUCCAUUGCUUUGACGAAAGAUGGCCAAGUUUAUUCAUGGGGAAAAGGUGACAACCAGAGACUUGGACAUGGAACAGAGGAACAUGUUCGUUAUCCAAAACUCUUAGAAGGCUUGCAAGGGAAGAAGGUGAUUGAUGUGGCUGCAGGCUCCACCCACUGCCUGGCUCUGACUGAGGACAGCGAGGUCCACAGCUGGGGGAGCAACGACCAGUGCCAGCACUUUGACACCUUGCGCGUGACCAAGCCAGAACCUGCAGCAUUGCCAGGACUGGACACCAAACACAUAGUGGGAAUUGCCUGUGGGCCUGCCCAGAGCUUUGCUUGGUCAUCAUGUUCUGAGUGGUCCAUUGGCCUCCGUGUCCCUUUUGUGGUGGACAUCUGCUCAAUGACUUUUGAGCAGCUGGAUCUCCUGCUUCGGCAGGUGAGUGAGGGGAUGGAUGGCUCCGCGGACUGGCCCCCGCCCCAGGAGAAAGAGUGUGUGGCCGUGGCAACGCUGAAUCUUCUACGACUUCAGUUGCAUGCUGCCAUUAGUCACCAGGUUGACCCGGAAUUCCUUGGUUUAGGUCUGGGCAGCAUCCUCCUGAACAGCCUGAAGCAGACGGUGGUGACCCUGGCCAGCAGUGCGGGCGUGCUGAGCACCGUGCAGUCGGCCGCCCAGGCCGUGCUGCAGAGUGGCUGGUCCGUGCUGCUGCCCACCGCGGAGGAGCGGGCCCGGGCACUCUCUGCUCUCCUGCCCUGCGCAGUUUCAGGCAAUGAAGUGAACAUAAGUCCAGGUCGUCGAUUCAUGAUUGAUCUUCUGGUGGGCAGCUUGAUGGCUGAUGGAGGGUUGGAGUCAGCCUUACACGCAGCCAUUACUGCAGAGAUCCAGGAUAUUGAAGCCAAAAAAGAAGCACAGAAGGAAAAAGAAAUUGAUGAACAGGAAGCGAAUGCCUCAACAUUUCAUAGAAGCAGGACUCCACUGGAUAAAGACCUUAUUAAUACGGGGAUCUGUGAGUCUUCUGGCAAACAGUGUUUGCCUCUGGUUCAGCUCAUACAACAGCUUCUUAGAAACAUUGCUUCUCAGACUGUAGCCAGAUUGAAAGAUGUUGCCCGUCGGAUUUCAUCAUGUCUGGACUUUGAGCAACACAGUCGUGAAAGAUCUGCUUCAUUGGAUUUGUUACUGCGUUUUCAACGUUUGCUUAUUAGUAAACUUUAUCCAGGAGAAAGUAUUGGUCAGACCUCAGAUAUUUCUAGUCCAGAGCUAAUGGGUGUUGGUUCCUUGCUGAAGAAGUACACAGCCCUCCUGUGCACGCACAUUGGAGAUAUACUGCCUGUGGCCGCCAGCAUUGCUUCUACCAGCUGGCGGCACUUCGCGGAGGUGGCUUACAUUGUGGAAGGGGACUUUACUGGUGUUCUCCUUCCAGAACUAGUAGUUUCUAUAGUGCUUCUGCUCAGUAAAAAUGCUGGUCUCAUGCAAGAGGCUGGAGCUGUACCUCUGCUGGGUGGCCUGUUGGAACAUCUGGAUCGGUUCAACCAUCUGGCACCAGGAAAGGAACGGGAUGAUCAUGAAGAGUUAGCCUGGCCUGGCAUAAUGCUUGCUCUGUUUUGCCCGGAAAUAGGUCAGUCUGCGGUAUUUUGUGGCCGUUCUGGAAAACAGCUGAAGCGUUGCCACAGCAGCCAGCCAGGCAUGCUGCUGGACAGCUGGUCCCGCAUGGUGAAGAGCCUGAAUGUGUCGUCCUCCGUGAACCAGGCAUCCCGUCUCAUUGACGGCAGCGAGCCCUGCUGGCAGUCAUCGGGGUCGCAAGGAAAGCACUGGAUUCGUUUGGAGAUUUUCCCAGAUGUUCUUGUUCAUAGAUUAAAAAUGAUCGUAGAUCCUGCUGACAGUAGCUACAUGCCGUCCCUGGUUGUAGUGUCAGGUGGAAAUUCCCUGAAUAACCUUAUUGAACUAAAGACAAUCAAUAUUAACCCUUCUGACACCACAGUGCCCCUUCUGAAUGACUGCACAGAGUAUCACAGGUAUAUUGAAAUUGCUAUAAAGCAGUGCAGGAGCUCAGGAAUCGAUUGUAAAAUCCAUGGUCUCAUCCUGCUGGGACGGAUCCGUGCAGAAGAGGAAGAUUUGGCUGCAGUUCCUUUCUUAGCUUCGGAUAAUGAAGAGGAGGAGGAUGAGAAAGGCAACAGCGGAAGCCUCAUUAGAAAGAAGGCUGCUGGGCUGGAAUCAGCAGCUACGAUAAGAACCAAGGUGUUUGUGUGGGGCCUGAAUGACAAGGACCAGCUGGGCGGGCUGAAAGGCUCCAAGAUAAAGGUUCCUUCGUUCUCUGAGACACUGUCAGCUUUGAAUGUGGUACAGGUGGCUGGUGGAUCUAAAAGUUUGUUUGCAGUGACUGUGGAAGGGAAGGUGUAUGCCUGUGGAGAAGCCACGAAUGGCCGGCUGGGGCUGGGCAUUUCCAGCGGGACGGUGCCCAUCCCACGGCAGAUCACAGCUCUCAGCAGCUACGUGGUCAAGAAGGUGGCUGUUCACUCAGGUGGCCGGCACGCGACGGCUUUAACUGUCGAUGGAAAAGUGUUUUCGUGGGGCGAAGGUGACGAUGGAAAACUUGGACACUUCAGCAGAAUGAACUGUGACAAACCAAGGCUGAUCGAGGCCCUGAAAACCAAGCGUAUCCGGGAUAUCGCCUGUGGGAGCUCGCACAGCGCAGCCCUCACAUCCAGCGGAGAACUGUACACCUGGGGCCUCGGCGAGUACGGCCGGCUGGGACAUGGGGAUAAUACGACACAGCUAAAGCCCAAAAUGGUGAAAGUCCUUCUCGGUCACAGAGUAAUCCAGGUUGCAUGUGGGAGUAGAGACGCGCAGACCCUGGCUCUGACCGAUGAAGGUUUGGUAUUUUCCUGGGGUGAUGGUGACUUUGGAAAACUGGGCCGGGGCGGAAGUGAAGGCUGUAACAUUCCCCAGAACAUUGAGAGACUAAAUGGACAGGGGGUGUGCCAGAUUGAGUGUGGAGCUCAGUUCUCCCUGGCGCUCACCAAGUCUGGAGUGGUGUGGACAUGGGGAAAGGGGGAUUACUUCAGAUUGGGCCACGGCUCUGACGUGCACGUGCGGAAACCACAGGUGGUGGAAGGGCUGAGAGGGAAGAAGAUCGUGCAUGUGGCUGUCGGGGCCCUGCACUGCCUGGCGGUCACGGACUCGGGGCAGGUGUAUGCUUGGGGUGACAACGACCACGGCCAGCAGGGCAAUGGCACGACCACGGUUAACAGGAAGCCCACACUCGUGCAAGGCUUAGAAGGCCAGAAGAUCACACGCGUGGCUUGUGGGUCGUCCCACAGUGUGGCGUGGACAACUGUGGAUGUGGCCACGCCCUCUGUCCACGAGCCCGUCCUCUUCCAGACUGCAAGAGACCCUUUAGGUGCUUCCUAUUUAGGCGUGCCUUCAGAUGCUGAUUCUUCUGCUGCCAGUAAUAAAAUAAGUGGUGCAAGUAAUUCUAAGCCAAAUCGCCCUUCUCUUGCCAAGAUUCUCUUGUCAUUGGAUGGAAAUCUGGCCAAACAGCAGGCCUUAUCGCAUAUUCUUACAGCAUUGCAAAUCAUGUAUGCCAGAGAUGCUGUUGUCGGGGCCCUGAUGCCGGCCGCCAUGAUCGCCCCGGUGGAGUGCCCCUCGUUCUCCUCGGCGGCCCCUUCCGACGCAUCUGCGAUGGCUAGUCCCAUGAAUGGAGAAGAAUGCAUGCUGGCUGUUGAUAUCGAAGACAGACUGAGUCCAAAUCCAUGGCAAGAAAAGAGAGAGAUUGUUUCCUCUGAGGACGCAGUGACCCCCUCUGCAGUGACUCCGUCGGCCCCCUCAGCCUCCGCUCGGCCUUUUAUCCCAGUGACGGAUGACCUGGGAGCCGCAAGCAUCAUUGCAGAAACCAUGACCAAAACCAAAGAGGAUGUUGAAAGCCAAAAUAAAGCAGCAGGUCCGGAGCCUCAGGCCUUGGAUGAGUUCACCAGUCUGCUGAUUGCGGAUGACACUCGUGUGGUGGUAGACCUGCUCAAGCUGUCAGUGUGCAGCCGGGCCGGGGACAGGGGCAGGGAUGUGCUCUCCGCGGUGCUUUCCGGCAUGGGGACCGCCUACCCACAGGUGGCAGAUAUGCUGUUGGAGCUCUGUGUCACCGAGUUGGAGGAUGUGGCCACAGACUCGCAGAGCGGCCGCCUCUCUUCUCAGCCUGUGGUGGUGGAGAGUAGCCACCCUUACACCGACGACACCUCCACCAGUGGCACAGUGAAGAUACCAGGUGCAGAAGGACUCAGGGUAGAAUUUGACCGGCAGUGCUCCACAGAGAGGCGCCACGACCCUCUCACAGUCAUGGACGGCGUCAACAGGAUCGUCUCCGUGCGGUCAGGCCGAGAGUGGUCCGACUGGUCCAGCGAGCUGCGCAUCCCAGGGGAUGAGUUAAAGUGGAAGUUCAUCAGCGAUGGGUCUGUGAAUGGCUGGGGCUGGCGCUUCACCGUCUAUCCCAUCAUGCCAGCUGCUGGCCCUAAAGAACUCCUCUCUGACCGCUGCGUCCUCUCCUGUCCAUCCAUGGACUUGGUGACGUGUCUGUUAGACUUCCGACUCAACCUUGCCUCUAACAGAAGCAUCGUCCCUCGCCUUGCGGCCUCGCUGGCAGCUUGUGCACAGCUGAGUGCCCUAGCUGCCAGUCACAGAAUGUGGGCCCUUCAGAGACUGAGGAAGCUGCUUACAACUGAAUUUGGGCAGUCAAUUAACAUAAAUAGGCUGCUUGGAGAAAAUGAUGGGGAAACAAGAGCUUUGAGUUUUACAGGUAGUGCUCUUGCUGCUUUGGUGAAAGGUCUUCCAGAAGCUUUGCAAAGGCAGUUUGAAUAUGAAGAUCCUAUUGUGAGGGGUGGCAAACAGCUGCUCCACAGCCCAUUCUUUAAGGUACUGGUAGCUCUUGCUUGUGACCUGGAGCUGGACACUCUGCCUUGCUGUGCCGAGACGCACAAGUGGGCCUGGUUCCGGAGGUACUGCAUGGCCUCCCGUGUUGCUGUGGCCCUUGACAAAAGAACACCGUUGCCCCGUCUGUUUCUUGAUGAGGUGGCUAAGAAAAUUCGUGAAUUAAUGGCAGACAGCGAAAACAUGGAUGUUCUGCAUGAGAGCCAUGACAUUUUUAAAAGAGAGCAAGACGAACAACUUGUGCAGUGGAUGAACAGGCGACCAGAUGACUGGACUCUCUCUGCUGGUGGCAGUGGAACAAUUUAUGGAUGGGGACAUAAUCACAGGGGCCAGCUCGGGGGCAUUGAAGGCGCAAAAGUCAAAGUUCCCACUCCCUGUGAAGCCCUUGCAACUCUCAGACCCGUGCAGUUAAUCGGAGGGGAACAGACCCUCUUUGCUGUGACGGCUGAUGGGAAGCUGUAUGCCACUGGGUAUGGUGCAGGUGGCAGACUAGGCAUUGGAGGGACAGAGUCGGUGUCCACCCCAACAUUGCUUGAAUCCAUUCAGCAUGUGUUUAUUAAGAAAGUAGCUGUGAACUCUGGAGGAAAGCACUGCCUUGCCCUGUCUUCAGAAGGAGAAGUUUACUCUUGGGGUGAGGCAGAAGAUGGGAAGUUGGGGCAUGGCAACAGAAGUCCGUGUGACCGCCCUCGUGUCAUCGAGUCUCUGAGAGGAAUUGAAGUGGUCGAUGUUGCUGCUGGCGGAGCCCACAGCGCCUGUGUCACAGCAGCCGGGGACCUCUACACAUGGGGCAAAGGCCGCUACGGCCGGCUGGGGCACAGCGACAGUGAGGACCAGCUGAAGCCGAAGCUGGUGGAGGCGCUGCAGGGCCACCGUGUGGUUGACAUCGCCUGUGGCAGUGGAGAUGCCCAGACCCUCUGCCUCACAGAUGACGACACUGUCUGGUCCUGGGGGGACGGGGACUACGGCAAGCUCGGCCGGGGAGGCAGCGAUGGCUGUAAAGUGCCUAUGAAGAUUGAUUCUCUUACUGGUCUUGGAGUAGUUAAAGUGGAAUGCGGAUCCCAGUUUUCUGUUGCCCUUACCAAAUCUGGAGCUGUUUAUACCUGGGGCAAAGGCGAUUAUCACAGGUUGGGCCAUGGAUCAGAUGACCAUGUUCGAAGGCCUCGGCAGGUCCAAGGGUUGCAGGGGAAGAAAGUCAUCGCCAUCGCCACUGGCUCCCUGCACUGUGUGUGCUGCACAGAGGAUGGUGAGGUUUAUACAUGGGGCGACAAUGAUGAGGGACAACUGGGAGACGGAACCACCAAUGCCAUCCAGAGGCCUCGGUUGGUAGCUGCCCUUCAGGGUAAGAAGGUCAACCGUGUGGCCUGUGGCUCAGCACAUACCCUCGCCUGGUCGACCAGCAAGCCCGCCAGUGCUGGCAAACUCCCUGCACAGGUCCCCAUGGAGUACAAUCACCUGCAGGAGAUCCCCAUCAUUGCGCUGAGGAACCGUCUGCUGCUGCUGCACCACCUCUCCGAGCUCUUCUGCCCCUGCAUCCCCAUGUUCGACCUGGAAGGCUCGCUCGACGAAACUGGACUCGGGCCUUCUGUUGGGUUCGACACUCUCCGAGGAAUUCUGAUAUCCCAGGGAAAGGAGGCGGCUUUCCGGAAAGUAGUACAAGCAACUAUGGUACGCGAUCGUCAGCAUGGCCCCGUCGUGGAGCUGAACCGCAUCCAGGUCAAACGAUCAAGGAGCAAAGGCGGGCUGGCCGGCCCCGACGGCACCAAGUCUGUCUUUGGGCAGAUGUGUGCUAAGAUGAGCUCGUUUGGUCCCGACAGCCUCCUCCUUCCUCACCGUGUCUGGAAAGUCAAGUUUGUGGGUGAAUCUGUGGAUGACUGUGGGGGCGGCUACAGCGAGUCCAUAGCUGAGAUCUGUGAGGAGCUGCAGAACGGACUCACGCCCCUGCUGAUCGUGACACCCAACGGGAGGGAUGAGUCUGGGGCCAACCGAGACUGCUACCUGCUCAGCCCGGCCGCCAGAGCACCCGUGCACAGCAGCAUGUUCCGCUUCCUGGGUGUGUUGCUGGGCAUUGCCAUCCGAACCGGGAGUCCCCUGAGCCUCAACCUUGCCGAGCCUGUCUGGAAGCAGCUGGCUGGGAUGAGCCUCACCAUCGCGGACCUCAGUGAGGUUGAUAAGGAUUUUAUUCCUGGACUCAUGUACAUCCGAGACAAUGAAGCCACCUCAGAGGAGUUUGAAGCCAUGAGCCUGCCCUUCACAGUGCCAAGUGCCAGUGGCCAGGACAUUCAGUUGAGCUCCAAGCACACACACAUCACCCUGGACAACCGCGCGGAGUACGUGCGGCUGGCGAUAAACUAUAGACUCCAUGAAUUUGAUGAGCAGGUGGCUGCUGUUCGGGAAGGAAUGGCCCGCGUUGUGCCUGUUCCCCUCCUCUCUCUGUUCACCGGCUACGAACUGGAGACGAUGGUGUGUGGCAGCCCUGACAUCCCGCUGCACCUUCUCAAGUCGGUGGCCACCUAUAAAGGCAUCGAGCCUUCCGCAUCGCUGAUCCAGUGGUUCUGGGAGGUGAUGGAGUCCUUCUCCAACACAGAGCGCUCUCUUUUCCUUCGCUUCGUCUGGGGCCGGACGAGGCUGCCCAGGACCAUCGCCGACUUCCGGGGCCGAGACUUCGUCAUCCAGGUGUUGGAUAAAUACAACCCUCCAGACCACUUCCUCCCUGAGUCCUACACCUGUUUCUUCUUGCUGAAGCUGCCCAGGUAUUCCUGCAAGCAGGUGCUGGAGGAGAAGCUCAAGUACGCCAUCCACUUCUGCAAGUCCAUAGACACAGAUGACUACGCUCGCAUCGCACUUACAGGAGAGCCAGCCGCCGACGACAGCAGCGACGAUUCAGAUAACGAGGAUGUCGACUCCUUUGCUUCGGACUCUACACAAGAUUAUUUAACAGGACACUAAGAUGGGGAAACGUCCUCGUGAGAUGAGAGCCUGAGCCAGGCAGCAGAGCACUCGCUGCUGUGUAGACUGUAGGCUGCCUGGUGUGUCUGAUGAGAAGCGUCCGUCCUCGAGCCAGGCGGGAGGAGGGAGUGGAGAGACUGACUGGCCGUGAUGGGAAUGACAGUGAGAAGGUCCGCCUGUGCGCGUGGAACACUGUGGACGCUCGACUUCCAAGGGUCUUCUCACCCGUAAUGCUGCAUUACAUGUAGGACUGUGUUUACUAAAGUGUGUAAAUGUUUAUAUAAAUACCAAAUUGCAGCAUCCCCAAAAUGAAUAAAGCCUUUUUACUUGUGGGUGCAAUCGAUUUUUUUUUCUUUCUCCUUUCUUUCAAGUGUCGUGAGUCGUCUUGAUUGUAUAUUGGAAAUAACUGUGUAACAAAUCGUAUUAUAAAUAUUUCAAUUAAUUUUACUCUGAAUUUGUUUAUUAAAAGACUUUUGAACAUGAAAUGAUUAGUAUUACUUGAAUGCAUCCAGAGGAUAUUUAAACCAAAAUGAAAAACCAGAAGGCCAUUUGGUGUCCCCUCUCCCAGGUGUCCCCUUGUAGCAUAUGCAUUAUGUCAUCUGAAUUGAGGCCUUUCUGUGAACAGCAUCAUAACUUCUAUCAUGGAAAGUGUACUAUAUAUAAUGUUUGUGUCAUGUAUAUGCCUAAAUUUUAAUUAUCUAUAAAUAAAACAUCUGACAUAAAA